AAGGAAGUAACCCACCAAAGUGAAAAAGAGGAACAAGUUCUAACCCAAUGCAGGUUUAAAACAUAACCAAAAGAACAAAAGAGAGAGCUUGACACACCAAUCUUGAGGUGUUGUGCCAUUCUCUGGGAACAUACAGAUGAAAUGACCUGAACCCUGCCCACCAUUUAACCAAGUAAGAAUACAAUUCUCUCUCAUUUAGGUUAUCACGCUAUAAUAGAGAAUGGACUCAUUAAUAUGGGAUUACAGAGGAAGGAAUGGUUAAGAAAAAGACAUGGCCUCUGACUGCUCCAAAAAAGGAUAAGCAGGGCUUCACAGAAGAGGUGACAGAAAAGGAAGUGGAAUGGAAUAAAAUCCCCCAAUACAGUACAAUUAUACAUUAAUGGCUGUAAUGUGAAGAGCAUCACACACGAAGAGAGCCAUCUUCCAGAAAUAAGUUUAUACACUCUCUCCUCUAAUUGCAUCAGGACUUUACCAGAUAAUGUUCUUCCAGAUCUGAAAAGGAAAAUGCCUAAAAGAGCUUCCAAACUCAUUUUUGAAUAAUACUAGGCUACAAAGAAUUACACUGUGAAUUCAUUAAGGGUAACACCAAAUCACUAAACAGCACUGUUUGUACAGAAAUGUCGAAAAGCUGUGGAAAUAAUUUAGCGGCCAUUUCUGUAGGAAUUUCGCUUCUUUUACUCUUAGUGGUUUGUGGAAUUGGGUGUGUUUGGCACUGGAAACACCGUGUUGCCACACGAUUUACCUUACCGAGGUUUUUACAAAGGAGAAGCAGCAGGAGAAAAGUCUGUACUAAAACAUUCUUGGGCCCCCGCAUCAUUGGCUUAAGGCAUGAAAUCUCAGUUGAAACCCAAGACCACAAAUCUGCUGUCAGGGGAAAUAACACACACGACAACUAUGAAAAUGUGGAAGCAGGUCCUCCCAAAGCUAAAGGAAAAACCGAUAAGGAACUAUAUGAAAACACAGGGCAGUCUAAUUUCGAGGAGCAUAUCUAUGGAAAUGAGACAUCUUCUGACUAUUAUAACUUCCAGAAGCCUCGUCCUUCUGAAGUUCCUCAAGAUGAAGAUAUAUACAUUCUUCCAGAUUCAUAUUAGCUUUUCAAAAUAUUGACUUUUGUUAUUGGAUGAUAAAUAUUCACUGUAAUUUUUCAACAGCAAAGACAAGGAAUCAAACUAAAUGUUGAUCAACUGUAGACUGGAUAAAGAAAAUGUGGUACACAUACACCAUAGAAUAUUAUGCAGCCGUAAAAAAAGAACAAAACUAACAUGGGAACAGAAAAUCAAAUACCACAUAUUCUCACUUAAAAGUGGGAGCUAAAUAAUAAGAACACAUGGAGAGAAGGAGAGGAACAACAGACACUGGGGCCUACUUGAGGGAGGACAGUGGAAGGAGGGAGAGGUUCAGGGAAAAAAAAAAUAUCAGGUACUAUGCUUAGUACACACAUGAUGAAAUAAUCUGUACACCAAACCCCCAAGUCACAAGUGUUCCUACAUAACAAACCUGAACAUGUACCCCUGAACAUAAAAUUAUAAUUAAAAUAUUAAAAAUAAUUCACUGUGAUUUUUAUUGUACUGAUGCCAUUCUUAAUCAAGUUCUGAUAAGUGGAUGGUCUCUGCCUAUCUCCACCUUUCUGAAUCCUAUGUGUAUCGCUGUGGAUUAAUUCUAGAUAUCUUCUCCACCCUCCUUGCACCAGACUAAAUCUGUAUUAUGUGAUAUUGAUUCUUCCUUCUAAAUAUUACCCGUUAUCUCUUUCCUUUAUUUCUACCAUUAUCUUUAUCUGGCUCAGAAUUAUUGUCAUAGGCUCCUAACUGUUCCUCCUGCUUCUAGUUUCUACCCACUCAAUCAAUUACCGAUGGUGUUGCCAGAUUUAUCUUCAGAAAAUAUUCCUAACAGCCACAUUAUUUCUUUCACUUAAAAUGUUUUAAUGCCCCCUCUUUGCAAAAGACAUAAUACCCAUAAUUUGAACUCCAAAAUUUAUGGUUUUCCACAAUUGGUUCCAAUUCACUUUUCCAGUGACUUCUCUUACUAUCUCUCAUUUCUUUGCCUUCAGCAGAAUCAUCUUAAAACCUGCCAAACUUAUCCUUCCUUCACAGCUUUGCUUUUCUGCCUCUUCUCUCAAGCCUGCUUCAGAUCAUAAGUUCUUCCACACAUCUCCUGAAUCACUCCAAACCCGCAUUUACCUUUUUAUUUUCUGAUAUAAGCUUUGAUGCCUCUUCAAUUCUUAGGACAUUUAAACAUAUGAAUGUUGCCACAGCAUUUUAUUACCUAGCUUCAUAUGAAAAUGUCUUAAAUUCCCACCUAAAUGAAAAGAAACUGCCCAAAUGCCUAGAACAUCACAUAAGGCACUAAAUGCCUCAUGUUUUACUGACGGGAAUUGAAUUGUACAUUUUGCUGAGUAGUUUUGAGAAAAAAAUCUAAUAAAUUCAUCUGUUAUUCAUCCAUACAAGGAAUAUUUGUUGUGUCUUCUAUCUACUUGCUAUUGUGCUGUGCACCUGAGGGACAUGGGUUGGUGGAGGGGUUACAAAAUUAAAAAGAGAGACAUGGAUCCUGAACACAUACAGUCUAGUAGGAAAGAAAACAUAGUAAACAAAUGAAUACGAUGCUGCUCAUGAAGCUAUGAUAGCUCAUCUCUAAAUCCACUCUUUUAUUUGCUCCUCUGAAUUGCUUGACCUGGGCCUCUGCAAACAUUUCUUUUGCCAGGUGGAUCCAUUCUAUUCUCUACCAAUAGGGGGCACUAAGGAAGACCGAAAGGCAGUAGGAGGCAACAGGGAAUUGCUCCUGCCUAUUCUUUCUGUUGCCCCCGCAGGAAUUUAUUGCCAUGUGGUUUACUCCAGCAUCACUGGUUGUUUGCAGCUUUCUAGUUUCUUCCAUCAUUCCCAGGACCAGCUUCUCUGCAACCUGUCAGAAGCACCAGCACCAGCCAGGUGGCACCCUCCCUUAGACUCUGACAGCCAGACUCUCCUUCAACCUCCUGAAGUGGUGCAGGAGACAAGUGGUACCCUCAGAGUUCUGCGUCCCAGCCUGGCAGGGCUCCUCCUCUGAGGUCUGGUAACUCUCAGCCAAGAUUGUUACAGUUACUAUCUCUGUGGUACCUGUGUCCCCUUUUUUGUUUUUCCAUCCUGCCAAUGCCUGUUUAGCCAAUUAUCUAUAUUAAAUUCUCUCUGUUAAAACAAA